CUGUUUCCGGGAGGCGCGUGGGGCUUGAGGCCGAGAACGGCCCUUGCUGCCACCAACAUGGAGACUUUGUACCGUGUCCCGUUCUUAGUGCUCGAAUGUCCCAACCUGAAGCUGAAGAAGCCGCCCUGGUUGCACAUGCCGUCGGCCAUGACUGUGUAUGCUCUGGUGGUGGUGUCUUACUUCCUCAUCACCGGAGGAAUAAUUUAUGAUGUUAUUGUUGAACCUCCAAGUGUCGGUUCUAUGACUGAUGAACAUGGGCAUCAGAGGCCAGUAGCUUUCUUGGCCUACAGAGUAAAUGGACAAUAUAUUAUGGAAGGACUUGCAUCCAGCUUCCUAUUUACAAUGGGAGGUUUAGGUUUCAUAAUCCUGGACCGAUCGAAUGCACCAAAUAUCCCAAAACUCAAUAGAUUCCUUCUUCUGUUCAUUGGAUUCGUCUGUGUCCUAUUGAGUUUUUUCAUGGCUAGAGUAUUCAUGAGAAUGAAACUGCCACGGAGUCUCGCUCUGUUGCCCAGGCUGGAGUGCAGUGGCGUGAUCUCGGCUCACUACAAACUCUGCCUCCCAGGGGCUAUCUGAUGGGUUAGAGUGCCUUUGAGAAGAAAUCAGUGGAUACUGGAUUUGCUCCUGUCAAUGAAGUUUUAAAGGCUGUACCAAUCCUCUAAUAUGAAAUGUGGAAAAGAAUGAAGAGCAGCAGUAAAAGAAAUAUCUAGUGAAAAAACAGGAAGCGUAUUGAAGCUUGGACUAGAAUUUCUUCUUGGUAUUAAAGAGACAAGUUUAUCACAGAAUUUUUUUUCCUGCUGGCCUAUUGCUAUACCAAUGAUGUUGAGUGGCAUUUUCUUUUUAGUUUUUCAUUAAAAUAUAUUCCAUAUCUACAACUAUAAUAUCAAAUAAAGUGAUUAUUUUUUACAACCCUCUUAACAUUUUUUGGAGAUGACAUUUCUGAUUUUCAGAAAUUAACAUAAAAUCCAGAAGCAAGAUUCCGUAAGCUGAGAACUCUGGACAGUUGAUCAGCUUUACCUAUGGUGCUUUGCCUUUAACUAGAGUGUGUGAUGGUAGAUUAUUUCAGAUAUGUAUGUAAAACUGUUUCCUGAACAAUAAGAUGUAUGAACGGAGCAGAAAUAAAUACUUUUUCUAAUUAA